GUCUCUGGGCGGCUGCUGCCGCUGCCGCUGCUGCUGCUGCGGGGGUCGGGCGGCGGCCAGGGGAUUUGGGCAGGCACCGUGGAUCCCCGAGAAGGGGACGAGUUGACAGAUGUGCGUGAGGAGGUCUCUGGUCGGCCUCACCUUUUGUACCUGCUACCUGGCUUCUUACCUCACGAACAAGUAUGUGCUGUCUGUCUUGAAAUUUACCUACCCUACAUUAUUCCAAGGGUGGCAGACGCUCAUUGGUGGACUUUUGCUUCAUGUGUCCUGGAAACUGGGCUGGGUAGAGAUCAACAGCAGUUCAAGAUCUCAUGUUCUUGUGUGGCUUCCUGCUUCAGUGCUGUUUGUGGGUAUAAUCUAUGCUGGGUCCAGAGCAUUGUCCAGACUGGCCAUUCCUGUGUUUCUCACUUUGCAUAAUGUAGCUGAAGUUAUCAUCUGUGGGUACCAGAAGUGUUUUCAGAAAGAGAAAACAUCUCCUGCAAAGAUCUGUAGUGCCCUCCUCCUCCUGGCCGCAGCAGGAUGCCUUCCCUUCAAUGACUCCCAGUUUAAUCCAGAUGGAUAUUUUUGGGCUAUAAUUCACUUACUCUGUGUAGGGGCUUAUAAAAUUCUACAGAAGUCCCAGAAACCCAGUGCAUUAAGUGACAUUGACCAGCAAUACUUAAACUAUAUAUUCAGUGUGGUGCUCCUGGCAUUUGCAUCUCAUCCCACAGGUGAUCUCUUCAGCGUCCUGGACUUCCCAUUCCUGUACUUCUACAGAUUCCAUGGUAGCUGCUGUGCCAGUGGAUUUUUGGGAUUCUUUCUCAUGUUCAGUACAGUGAAGCUAAAAAACCUUCUGGCCCCAGGGCAGUGUGCAGCCUGGAUUUUCUUUGCUAAGAUAAUCACAGCUGGCUUAUCAAUAUUGCUGUUUGAUGCGAUCCUGACCAGUGCAACCACGGGAUGGACUCCUGGAGUAGUGUCUCCAUCCACUUGAGAUGACACCAGGUGACUGGCCCUGAGAUCACCCACACCCAGAGAGUAUUUGGAUGCACUUCUAAACGCAAGCUGCUGAAACAGUGGCAGUAGAGAAUGAGCCAAACUGCGUGGAACGUCAUGUUCAAAAUCACGAAGUGAUUGUCAAAAAUCCGAGACAAAUACAUAGAAAGAGAGCAGAUGUUGCAAUAUCCUGGGUGAAAUGUCAAAAUCACGAAGCGACUGUCAAAAAUCUGAGACAAAUACAUAGAGAGCAGAUGCUGCAAAAUCUUGGGUGAAAUGUCAAACUCUUGUUUUGUAUUAGUUUUUUUUUUUUUUUUUUGAAACGGAGUCUUGGUCUUAUCGCCCAGGCCGGGGUACAGUGGCGUGAUCUCGGCUCACUGCAACCUCUGCCUCCCGGGUUCAAGCGAUUCUCCUGCCUCAGCCUCCUGAGUAACUGGGAUUACAGGCACCUGCCACCACACCUGGCUAAUUUUUGUAUUUUUUAGUAGAGACGGUUUUGCCAUGUUGGCCAGAAUGGUCUCAAACUCCUGACCUCAGGUGAUCCACCCGCCUUGGCCUCCCAAAGUGCUGGGAUUACAGGCAUGAGCCACCGAGGCCUGUGUUAGUUUUAUGAGAAAAAAAUGAAUUGUAAAAGAGGCUUUAAAGAGGUGAAUUGUAUGGUGUUGGAAUUCUAAUAGUGCUGUUAACAACAACAAAAAGACCAAAAAAAAAAAAAAAAAAAAACACCAAACCCACACCCAAAACAACCCUCCCUCCCCCACACAGCACAAUCAGGCAUUUCAGGCCUUGAUGUGAACACUUAACCUAAAGCUGGCAGGAUGCUCCUCAGCUACUGCCCAGGCCUGUGCGCCUGAGGGCGCCCUUCAAGCCUCAGGGAAGUGCCACAAUAAUAGGGAAGUGCGGAGCUACUGUGCUUCUAAUGUGAUGUGACAUUUUCUUAAAGAGGCCCCCUCCUCAGAACUGAAUAAGCCUCAGGCACCUUGAAACCUGAGGCCAUGGAAAGGGUCUUGCAUUAGCUUCCCAACAAAUCCACCCUGCAGACAGGUAACAAGUGCCUAAAUCAUCCAGGUAACUUUUAAUGGAAAUAGAUAUAUAUAUAGUUCUAUAUUCUAUAUAAAUUAUAAUAAAUAUAUGAGUAUGUUAUUAAAUUAUAACUUAUCUAUAUUUAUAAAUAUAUAUUUAUACUGUAUGUAUAUUGGGGGACAGGCAGAAUCUAAUCACCUACCUCAUGGAAGGCUGAAUUAGUCUUUCUUUCAUUGAGUCAAUUACUUCCCACUGCUCAGCAUCUCAUGCUGUACUGAAAAAUUAAGUUCUAUGAUACAUUCCCCCAACACUGGGGAGAUGUAGGGGUAGAGGGAGGGCUUUCUCUACAAGUACUUAGAUUUUAAUAUUCGGUAAAUAAAAAAUAGGCAUUUUAUCAUGGAGAUUAAUCCAAGAGGUUUCUCUUGAGGUUUACAUGCUUAUGCAUAUCAUAAACAAUGUUAGUCGGUUUUCUUUUUGAUGUGAACACAGUGCAAGAGGGAUUUCUUACAGAAGAAAAGAAUCCAGAAAUCCAUUCAGGUAACUGAAUUUUGUUGGCAUUAUCUCAGCUCUCCCACUUACUUUCUCCUCUUAAUUGCCUUCCACACCCAUAAAGAGGGGGAAAAAAACACAAAAACCCACUACCGACCUGGGCUGCCACGUUCUAAUGAUACAUAACCACUCUCUCAUGAAGCUUUAAUUAUAUGCCAAGAGGUGCAGAGAGCUGGAAGCAUCCGCCCUCCCCUGAGACACACCAUCACCCAGCAAGAGUCUGCACGUAGCCAGGUGGCUCAACAUUCUCUGUUCUGUGGUCACCUUCUAGAAACUUGAAGACCAAACCACCGGGCCAGCUGCAAUUUGUUUUGCACACCUGCCCCAGGAAUUUUUUUUUUGAGACAGAGUUUCAUUCUCGUCACCCAGGCUGGAGUGCAAUAGUGUGAUCUCAGCUCACUGCAACUUCUGCCUCCUGGGUUCAAGCGAUUCUCCUGCCUCAGCCUCCUGAGUAGCCAGGAUUACAGGCGCCUGCCACUACACCUGGCUCAUUUUGUUGUAUUUUUAGUAAAGAUGGUGUUUCACCACGUUGGUCAGGCUGCUCUUGAACUCCUGACCUCAGGUGAUCCACCCGCCUCGGCCUUCCAAAGUGCAGGGAUUACAGGCGUGAGCCACUGCACCUGGCCCGGAAUUUUUUUUUAAGUUCAAAAUCUCACCCUUGACCUUCUACAGUAGGUAACAGUGGGAGUGACUUGCAUGGAUCAAAGUUUAAAAAUACAGAUAUGGGUGCAAGGCUAAUUUGAAAAGGGUGCCACUUGCACACUAAAUGACAGGCUUCACCUCUGGAAGCUUCCCACUCUAAGACAUGUCCUGACUGUGGCGACGAGGGGCCUUUUUAUAUUACACUUAGGACACACACGCACAAAGAUAAACAUUCAGCUACAUCAUGGCUGGUUAAUAUCACCUACACCAGGACUCAGAAGUCCCACUCCUAGGUAUUUACCCCAAGAGAAAUUAAAAAGUAUUUCCACAGAAAGCCAUGCACAAGAACAUUCAUGGCAGCCGCAUGAACAAAUAUCUAUCAACAGGAGGAGGGAUAAACAAACUGUACUACAUCUUAUAUCACUGAGCAUUUUUAUUUUUAUUUUUUUGAGACGUAGUUUCGCUUGUCGCCCAGGCUGAAGUGAAUAGUGUGAUCUCGGCUCACUGCAACCUCCACCUCCCGGGUUUAAGCGAUUCUCCUGCCUCAGCCUGCAGGGUAGCUGGGAUUACAGGUGCCUGCCACUAUGCCCAGCUAAUUUUUGUAUUUUUAGUAGAGACAGAGUUUCAUCACGUUAGCCAGGCUGGUCUUAAACUCUUGACCUCAAGUGAUCCCCCCACCUUACCCACCUCGGCCUCCCAAAGUGCUGGGAUUUAUAGGCGUGAUCCACUGCACGUGGCCCACUCAGCAAUUAAAAAAAAAAAUCUACUGACACACAUGACAUGGGGAAAUCUCACAUGUUAAGUUGUAUGAAGGAAGAUGGACCCCAAAAAGUAUAUGCCAUGAUCCUAUUCACAUGAAGUUUCAGAAUAGGUAAAACUAAUCUAUGGUGACAGAAGUGAGAAUAGUAAUUGCUUUUGCAGGAAGGGGAUGGGAAGAAUGGGAUGGGGAGGAGAACUUUCUGCAGGGACAGAAAUGCUCUAUAUCUGGAUCAGAGCAGUGGUUACAGAAUUCAUGGAAAUGCACACUUCAAACAAACAAGUGCAUCUGAUUGUCUGUAAAUUACUCCUUUUAGCGGCUGCAGCAGGAUUUGAUGGGUGAAAGGAUUAGCUCAUCACUUUGAGAGCUGCUUCAUUCAGCAGAGGCAUCUCAGAGUCUGAUUUCCACAGGAACAGGACAUCCCAAAACAGGGGAGGACAGUCCCAGGAUUUCAGGUGGGCGCCUCUGCUGGGCUGGCCACAUUGGACUGCCCUGGGGGCCCGAGGAAGACGGGACAGGCAGCAGGACUCUGGGGCUUUGGAAGCUAAUACUAAGGGAGGUGAGCAGCUCUGCAUAAUUGGCCUGUGACCAACAAGCCUGCUCCUUCCCCAAUCACUGAGCAUUCCCACCCAGGAGGGAAUCUGCCCUCUGUCUGGGCAGAGAUCCUCACACUAGCCUAGUGGCCAAAUGUGCCCCAGGCCCUCAAAGAGGGCAUUCCACAACCUGGCUCAAAGGAGCCAGGGUCUUUGGAGCCAGGGCCUGUUUCAGCGGCAGCUCCCUGUGCCUGGGGCCGAGUCAGUGGGGAGGGAGGGUUUGUCGGCAUCAUCAUUUGUGGGCUCUGCCUCCUGCCUGUGUGUGUGUAGGGGGAAGGGCAACGACUUCUACAGUUAGAAAAAUCUAUUUUAUGCAAAACCAACCCCCUUCCUACUUUGGGGUCUUUCCACUGGGCUCUCCCUACCAAAACCUGGUGGGGCCAACCACUCUCAGCCCUCAGUGCUUGCUUCAGUGCCAUUCCUCGGGGAAGUCUUCCUUGAGGCCUACCCCCUGGGGCCCACGUCCAACCCUUCCAUCAUUUCCUGCCGCUGUUUUUGUUUUGUUUUGUUGAGACAGGGUCUUGCUUUAUUGUCCAGGCUGGAGUGCAGUGGCACAAUCUCAGCUCACUGCAGCCUCUGCCUCCUGGGUUCAAGCAAUUCUCCCACCUCAGCCUCUCCAGUAGCUGGGACUACAGGCGCGCAACACCACACCUGGCUAAUUUUUUUAUUUUUAGUAGAGAUGGGGUUUUACCACGUUGGCCAGGCUGGUCCCAAACUCCUGACCUCAGGUGAUCCACCUGCCUUGGCCUCCCAAAGUUCUGGGAUUACAGGCGUGAGCCACCAUGCCUGGUCUCCUGCUGCUUUUCUAAGAUGGUUCCUUCCUCACGAUUAUGGUGCUCUGUCUCCUUGUUUACUGUUUACUCUCUGACAUCCCCACUCACUCCAAGGUGGAGGAGAAGAGGGGUUGUGGCUGGUUAGUUCUCUACUGGGUAAGGAAGCUUGGCUCAUAAUAAGGCCUCAAUCAAUACUUGGUUCAACAGGCGAAUUCUAUACCUGUUCCCCAACACACAAAAAUAAAGCAAACACCCCAGCGCCCCCACCCCCAACUGCCCCACUCUGUUUCCUACAAGUUCAAUGCAAAUGCAUGAGAAACGGCCUGUAACCCAUGUCGGCUUCUAGGAAAGAAGUCUCCAGGGAGCUGGGGGGUUGAGGCCCUUUGUAAUACACAACACACUGUCAAGAACUUAGACGAGAAUUCUGAAACGUGGAUUUCCCACAUUUUAUCAAAGUGCCAACAUCUGUGGCCAGAAUAGGAAACAUAGGUCUCCAGGAGCCGACCAGGAAAAUGCAGUCCAUGCGCAAUUCCAUUCUCUAUAGCAUGGACUAUUCCCAGAAGCACUGACUGCAGAGCCAAUGCAGUGAAAUUAAAAAUGAUCCACUUGGGAACAUCAAAUGAGGAGGGCAGGACAUACAUGCUGACUUGGCAAGUCUUCUAGCACAGUCUAAGGAGGAAAAGUUGUAUGUGUAUACGUGCACACGCACAUACACACAUACUGCGGCCUGGAACCUCAAGGCUCACAAUGAAAUCAUUUAAAGAAAAAAAAGAUCAGAUAAAAAAGAUCAGAUCUAGCACCAGCCCAACACUAGGCCUAUAAAAGGAGAGGUCGGCAUUAUCACCAGGCACGUGUCUGUUAGGACAGCUCCCGCCAACAUCGAAAUAGUGUACCUUCCUAUUCUCUUGGUUACCUAGAAAUCUGCUACACUGUUGGCCCAAAGAAUGAUCUUCAUGUCCAACCCCGAGGUCGGCAGUUGUGGGGCUGACUGCUGAGGAAUGUGGAAUUCAGAGACAGCUGGGCAACGUGAAAACAGCCUCGAGCCAGGAGCUCUAGCCUGGAUCCCCCAUUUCCUGUCUAUCAACUAGGAAAGCCUCACUUGGACUCCCUGAGCCAGUUUCCUGGCCAUGUUGCUUAAUAAAUAAAGUGAAUUUUAAUAAGUAAGGCAGUGAACCACAUAAAGCAUCCUUAUUCUUACACCAGUUGCUCCCUCCUUGACAUCAGGGCAAUCAUUCUGGUCAUUUAUUGAACACUUAUUACGUGCUUGCCUCUGCCAAAGAUGAAUAUGCCCUGGUUUUUUAAAUAAACAGAUCAUAGAGUGGAAGAAAAGUAA